CCUCUCGACGUCGGCCUGUGGGGAGCGAUGCCGACAAGCAGGAGCGGUCCCGGCUUCGGAAAGGGCCCACCCUGAGGAAUGGUCCGGCCGGGCCUAGCGAGGAUGUCCCUACCGCGAUGCUGGUUCCGUUACCCAGGGUGGACAGGCGCGGAAGCGGGACGGGGAAGAGCGAUAGUUUCGCGGCGUUUGCCCAGCCUCAACCCCUGGGAUGCGGGUGAGAGACAUGGAGGACUGGUCAGAAUUUGCGCGUCCCUGGGGCCGCACAAAAGGCUCCCAGCCGGCCUCCCGCAAUGUCCUCACCUGUACCUGGCAGCCGACCCCCUGGAUCCGCAGCGCCGCCAGGAGAAGUCCUGCGCAGCGCUGGGAAACGACAAAAGAAGGCAGCCUGACGGGCAGCGACAGCCACAGCAACAGCAACAGCCCCACUGCCGCCGGGGAUUCCAGGUUGCCGAGGAGCCCAAGUAGAAGAAAUAUGGAGUUUAGAGCCUGAGAAUUUUGAAAAAUUAAAGCCAGUUCAUGGGUUAAUUUUUCUUUUCAAGUGGCAGCCAGGAGAAGAACCAGCAGGCUCUGUGGUUCAGGACUCCCGACUUGACACGAUAUUUUUUGCUAAGCAGGUAAUUAAUAAUGCUUGUGCUACUCAAGCCAUAGUGAGUGUGUUACUGAACUGUACCCACCAGGAUGUCCAUUUAGGCGAGACAUUAUCAGAGUUUAAAGAAUUUUCACAAAGUUUUGAUGCAGCUAUGAAAGGCUUGGCACUGAGCAAUUCAGAUGUGAUUCGACAAGUACACAACAGUUUCGCCAGACAGCAAAUGUUUGAAUUUGAUACGAAGACAUCAGCAAAAGAAGAAGAUGCUUUUCACUUUGUCAGUUAUGUUCCUGUUAAUGGGAGACUGUAUGAAUUAGAUGGAUUAAGAGAAGGACCGAUUGAUUUAGGUGCAUGCAAUCAAGAUGAUUGGAUCAGUGCAGUAAGGCCUGUCAUAGAAAAAAGGAUACAAAAAGACGGGUUUUCACCAUGUUGCCCAGGCUGGUCUCAGACUCCUGAGCUCAAGCCAUCCGCCUGCCUCGACCUCCCAAAGUGGUACAGUGAAGGUGAAAUUCGAUUUAAUUUAAUGGCCAUUGUGUCUGACAGAAAAAUGAUAUAUGAGCAGAAGAUAGCAGAGUUACAAAGACAACUUGCAGAGGAGGAACCCAUGGAUACAGAUCAAGGUAAUAGUAUGUUAAGUGCUAUUCAGUCAGAAGUUGCCAAAAAUCAGAUGCUUAUUGAAGAAGAAGUACAGAAAUUAAAAAGAUACAAGAUUGAGAAUAUCAGAAGGAAGCAUAAUUAUCUGCCUUUCAUUAUGGAAUUGUUAAAGACUUUAGCAGAACACCAGCAGUUAAUACCACUAGUAGAAAAGGCAAAAGAAAAACAGAACGCAAAGAAAGCUCAGGAAACCAAAUGAAGAUGUUUUCAGAUAUGUACACAUUUCUGCUUCUGCACAUAUUUUCAUGGAAACCAUUAUGUAUAAAGAACUUAGAGCAACAUCCUAAUUGGCUCAGUGCACGUUUGGCAAUAGUGCCAGCCUGUCUUGUCUUUAAUGCAUGGAUUCAUAAACUUCUUCCCUACCUGCAUCAUGUGCAUGUAGUGCAUAUUAAAUGAAAGUGAUAUUAAGAAUGCUUUCCCAAAUUCCAUUAUUUGACAUUGAGUCUGACAACUGUUAGUUUUCUGGUUGUCUAACUACCAUAUGAAGCUAGAAAAUGCACAAACGAUAUUCCUUAUCUGUAAUUUAAAUACUUAAAAUUUGCAAUUGUCAGAUCUUGAUUAAACUGGUUGUCUUAUUUCUUCUCAUCAUUAACGGAAAAAAAAUCAGUAUUUCUAUCUUUGAUAUCUAAGUGUUUUGAGGAUUUUAAAACUGAAUUUUAUCUGCUAUACCAGUUAUUUGAGAAAGUAUGAUUUUAAUGUAAAUCAUUUAAAAAGGACAAAAGUAUAAUUUCCAGUGAUUUUCACUGCUGUCAGUAGAAAAGUAAUAAACAUCUCAAUUUUAUUUUAGUAAAUUUUCUUCAAGUGUUUGGGGUUAUUUGUUUAUGUAUUAGAGAAUUGUUUCAGGAAGGUCUGAGUAUUAUGCUUCAAAGCAAAAUUUCAGGUUAAGAAGAAAUUGUAAAUCUUAAAGAAUGUUGGUGUUACUCUCAAUGGAAUAUUGUUUCAAGCUUGUAAGCUGUGUAUAAAAAAACUGGAGGUCUGACAGUUCAUGUUAUCUGCUUUUUUAAAAAGAUGGUAGUGGUGAUGGGGGUCUUUCUAUGCCAAUUUGAAUAAAUUUCGUACAGCCUGCAGUUUUCAAGAGCCAUAUGUAAUUUGCUCACAAUUGAUUUUUAAAAAUUGAUUUGGGAGUUGCUUUGUAAUAAUCUUCUGCUUCUAAUCUUCCUUUGCAAGUCAGACUUUAAAGAAGACUUUAUAAAGCUUUCUUUUUUAAAGGAAGUAACCUACUUUUUUCUUUAUCAAGAAUAUUUCUGAGGUUGAUACAUGACUUUAACAUUUUAUUAUUUAUUGUAAAAUCAAUUUAGCAUAAUUUAUUUUAUUAGGGAGAAUGUGUACCCAUCUUCCAGCUUCAGCACAUUUUUAAGGAUUGUUUUUAAGCUUAGUAAUUGUGGUAUUAAAUGACUUAGAACUAAUGGAGAAAAACCUGAUAGGAAAUUGAUAGAAAAACGAAUGAAAUAUUUUUCAUACAUAAUUUCAGUUGGAGGUAAUGGAAAAUAUGUAGUCUCUCAGUUAUUUGUGGGUAAAUAUGUUUUGCUGUUGAUACAGUAAUAAUUAUGGAGUGUUUUCAAAGCCAUGAUAUAAUUUUUAAAAAUAGAUUUUUAAGGAAGGCUCAUCUUGAUCUCAUUCGUUUAUUUCAGCUUAAUUUAUAUAUUCUUUCCUAUUGAGGCUUAAAUUUUGUUAAGCAAUGUGAGGAUUAUUGUGGUAAGUUGUAUUUAGUAAUCAAUACAGUGUGAUACUGGCACUAGGAUUGACAAAUAAAGCAAUGGAACAGAAGAGAGAGCCUGAAAACAGAUCAACGUUUAUAUGAUCACUUGAUUUCGACAAAGGUGGCAAAACAAUUCAACAGAGAAGGAAAGUCUUUUCAACAAAUGGAGCCAGAAUAGAAUAGCUGAAUAUCCAUAUAGAAAAAAGUGAACAAUGACCCCCUACCUCACAAAAAUGACUUUGAGAUGAAUCAUAGACCUAAAUGUAAUAUUUUAAAAGUAUGAAGCUUUUUAACUGAAAACAGAUGAUAUUUUUGUGACUUGGGGGGUUAGCCAAAGGUUUCUUAGGUCACAGAAAGCAGUAACCAUAAAAGAUCCAAAAUUAGAGCUCAUCAGAAUUGUCAUUGAAAGUGUUAACAAAAGUAAUAUCAAAUGACAUUUGAAAAAUAUCCUUGUAAAAUGACUAUAUUAAUAGGUAUAAGGAUUUUUCUUAUUAAUCUAAUAAAAUUCCUUAAUAGGAAUUUCCAUAGCUUAAGAGUGGUUUAUUUUAUCUGCAUCUUCUUUGGUGAUUGCAAAUCCCUUGUGAUACUUCAUGAUUACUUCUGUCUGUGAAUAAAGAAGUGUGACUUGUCUGGGUGCUAUAUGUUGCUGGUUUGAAAUUAAGUCAUGAAGCUAGAGGGUAGAGAAAAUGGAAGAAUAAAGAGCAACCCAUAAAUAGAUAAAUGCUAUUUGGAAAGUUUUUUUUAAAUGAUAUUUUAUAGAAAAUCUUGCUCAUUUCAUAUUUAGUCUUUUCUAAAAUUUUAUUUAAUUAUUGGGUAGGUGAAGUCGCUUCCAUUCUAUUUUAAGCCUUCAAAAUAGCCAAUUCUAAGGGAUGUACUUCUGUUAUUAUCAACAAAAACCUUGCCAACAGCUGCGGCACUGGCUACUCUCACCUUAUAUGUUUAGUUCCCAAGAUAGCUUGCCCUUUUCCGAACAGCAGUCAGCUCGACUGUGCCACUAAAACAGACAAAUAUUUGCUCGGGAAUCACAACCACGGGGACUUGCUCCCCCAGUUAGGACCAUGGUACAUAUUUGUGUGUAUAUUAUGGUGUUACAUGCAGAUUAAUACUUUCAAUUAAUCCUCCUAGUUGCCUGUAACGUUAACAUUUCAAGAUGCAUUUAGAUAUUUUUAUCCUGUAGGAGGAUUUUGUUUAUUUGAGGGAAAAAAAGGGCUUUUAAUGUAUUCUCCUCAAAAACCAUUUAGAGAAAACAGAUAAGUAAAAAUAAAAUUUAAAUUACCAUAUUUCUAUUUACAGGGAUGAGCACAUUAACAUUUUAUGUAUUUAGUGAUCCUUUUUCCUCAUGUGUACACAUAUGUUUUUGUGUGUUAGUCUUGCUUGCCCUCCCCAUAGUCUGAAAUAGUUCUAUGAAGUUUAUAUUAUUUUUAAACUUGAUCAUAUACAAAUUUUCAGGAAACAAACCACUCUAGCUAUUUGAAGAGGAAUGCAGAUUUAUAUUGGGAGUUUUGAAACUACAUAGUUUCUUACAAAAUCAUUGGAAGGUUUGGAGGAGCGGUUUCAAGCUUAAGUCUCCAGAGAUUACUCCCAUCCAAACAUACAGUAUUGGUGUACCUAGGGAACUGCUCACUUUUGCAACAGUCAGGGAGUUCACUGUUGGAACUAUUAAUGUUAGAACAUGUUGCAGUAGUUGUGUUCAAGGAAUGAGGAACCUGCUGUAACACUUAAUGACUGUGCACUGGAAUGCAGAAAAGUUAAACCUUCUAUGCCUAAAUGCCUAAAACAGACAAACUGGAUAGUUAUAUUUUUAGAAUGAUACUGCGUUUUUUAGAGUAGUAUGAAUUCCUAGAUCAGUCAAACAUGCAUGUUAUUUAGUUUGUUCUUUAGUAUAUUGUUAACUGGCCUAAAUCCAAUGACUGACAUGGUAAAGAUUCACCACUUCUAGCAUACUGGGCACUUUUUAUUUUUGACUUGAUUACAUUAACUUUUUGAAAACUAUUCAGUGAUUUAUUCAGCCAAUCUUAUGAGGUACAUCUGAGUUGUUCUAGAUGCUAGAGGAUAGUAUAACAGGAAAAAGCCCCUGCUCUCAUGGUGAGACAGAUAAUAAGUAUGUAAUACAACUUUUCAAAUAGUAGUAUGAAUGGUAAAAAAAAUAGGGAAAAGGGGUGGGAGGAGCUGAGGUUUGAUAGAAUGGUCAUGGAAGAUCCCAUUAAUGAGAUGUACUUUAAGUAGAGACCUAAAUGAAGAUAAUUUUUUCUCUAGUACUGAACUAGCACUGUACAAGUGGAUUGCAUAUAGGCAUAUAGGCAGAACUUCUCUAGUACUGAACUAACACUGUACAAGUGGAUUGCAUAUAGGCAUAUAGGCAGAACCAAUGUGCAAUAAUUAAGAAUAUUAAUUUGCAAUCAUGUUUGAUGGUUAAAUGGUUUAUUAAUGUUGGAGUGUCAAUAUGAAAAUGGGUUGAAUAAAAGAUAUAUGGAAAUGCCUAGGACUACUGCUCUAUUUACUUUUUAGCUUAUCCAUAUAUUUUAUGUAAUAUGCUUCUUUGAUUCUUUCUUGUAGCAAUGAUAAUAUAAUAUUGAAUAAACCAUAAAACCAGUGGG